ACUCUGCACAUGCGGCUGGGUGGCAGCCAGCGGCCUCAGACAGACCCACUGGCGUCUCUCUGCUGAGUGACCGUAAGCUCGGCGUCUGGCCCUCUGCCUGCCUCUCCCUGAGUGUGGCUGACAGCCACGCAGCUGUGUCUGUCUGUCUGCGGCCCGUGCAUCCCUGCUGCGGCCGCCUGGUACCUUCCUUGCCGUCUCUUUCCUCUGUCUGCUGCUCUGUGGGACACCUGCCUGGAGGCCCAGCUGCCCGUCAUCAGAGUGACAGGUCUUAUGACAGCCUGAUUGGUGACUCGGGCUGGGUGUGGAUUCUCACCCCAGGCCUCUGCCUGCUUUCUCAGACCCUCAUCUGUCACCCCCACGCUGAACCCAGCUGCCACCCCCAGAAGCCCAUCAGACUGCCCCCAGCACACGGAAUGGAUUUCUGAGAAAGAAGCCGAAACAGAAGUCAUUCAAAACAAUGGCUGGUGUGCCCAUUUCGCAGAUGAGGCAAUGAGGCUGCGAGAGGUAGAGUGAUUUUCCCUCGGUGACUCAACUGGGACGUAGCAGGUCGGGCAGUCAAGCCAGGUGACCCCAUGAGCUGUCGCUGCAUCUUUCUCAUGAAGCACGGGGAACGGGUCGGAUGGCCCGUGGGAGUCAGCAUGCCGCGUGGCUGGGCCGCCCCCUUGCUCCUGCUGCUGCUCCAGGGAGGCUGGGGCUGCCCCGACCUCGUCUGCUACACCGAUUACCUCCAGACGGUCAUCUGCAUCCUGGAAAUGUGGAACCUCCACCCCAGCACGCUCACCCUUACCUGGCAAGACCAGUAUGAAGAGCUGAAGGACGAGGCCACCUCCUGCAGCCUCCACAGGUCGGCCCACAAUGCCACGCAUGCCACCUACACCUGCCACAUGGAUGUAUUCCACUUCAUGGCCGACGACAUUUUCAGUGUCAACAUCACAGACCAGUCUGGCAACUACUCCCAGGAGUGUGGCAGCUUUCUCCUGGCUGAGAGCAUCAAGCCGGCUCCCCCUUUCAACGUGACUGUGACCUUCUCAGGACAGUAUAAUAUCUCCUGGCGCUCAGAUUACGAAGACCCUGCCUUCUACAUGCUGAAGGGCAAGCUUCAGUAUGAGCUGCAGUACAGGAACCGGGGAGACCCCUGGGCUGUGAGUCCGAGGAGAAAGCUGAUCUCAGUGGACUCAAGAAGUGUCUCCCUCCUCCCCCUGGAGUUCCGCAAAGACUCGAGCUAUGAGCUGCAGGUGCGGGCAGGGCCCAUGCCUGGCUCCUCCUACCAGGGGACCUGGAGUGAAUGGAGUGACCCGGUCAUCUUUCAGACCCAGUCAGAGGAGUUAAAGGAAGGCUGGAACCCUCACCUGCUGCUUCUCCUCCUGCUUGUCAUAGUCUUCAUUCCUGCCUUCUGGAGCCUGAAGACCCAUCCAUUGUGGAGGCUAUGGAAGAAGAUAUGGGCCGUCCCCAGCCCUGAGCGGUUCUUCAUGCCCCUGUACAAGGGCUGCAGCGGAGACUUCAAGAAAUGGGUGGGUGCACCCUUCACUGGCUCCAGCCUGGAGCUGGGACCCUGGAGCCCAGAGGUGCCCUCCACCCUGGAGGUGUACAGCUGCCACCCACCACGGAGCCCGGCCAAGAGGCUGCAGCUCACGGAGCUACAAGAACCAGCAGAGCUGGUGGAGUCUGACGGUGUGCCCAAGCCCAGCUUCUGGCCGACAGCCCAGAACUCGGGGGGCUCAGCUUACAGUGAGGAGAGGGAUCGGCCAUACGGCCUGGUGUCCAUUGACACAGUGACUGUGCUAGAUGCAGAGGGGCCAUGCACCUGGCCCUGCAGCUGUGAGGAUGACGGCUACCCAGCCCUGGACCUGGAUGCUGGCCUGGAGCCCAGCCCAGGCCUAGAGGACCCACUCUUGGAUGCAGGGACCACAGUCCUGUCCUGUGGCUGUGUCUCAGCUGGCAGCCCUGGGCUAGGAGGGCCCCUGGGAAGCCUCCUGGACAGACUAAAGCCACCCCUUGCAGAUGGGGAGGACUGGGCUGGGGGACUGCCCUGGGGUGGCCGGUCACCUGGAGGGGUCUCAGAGAGUGAGGCGGGCUCACCCCUGGCCGGCCUGGAUAUGGACACGUUUGACAGUGGCUUUGUGGGCUCUGACUGCAGCAGCCCUGUGGAGUGUGACUUCACCAGCCCCGGGGACGAAGGACCCCCCCGGAGCUACCUCCGCCAGUGGGUGGUCAUUCCUCCGCCACUUUCGAGCCCUGGACCCCAGGCCAGCUAAUGAGGCUGACUGGAUGUCCAGAGCUGGCCAGGCCACUGGGCCCUGAGCCAGAGACAAGGUCACCUGGGCUGUGAUGUGAAGACACCUGCAGCCUUUGGUCUCCUGGAUGGGCCUUUGAGCCUGAUGUUUACAGUGUCUGUGUGUGUGUGUGCAUAUGUGUGUGUGUGCAUAUGCAUGUGUGUGUGUGUGUGUGUCUUAGGUGCGCAGUGGCAUGUCCACGUGUGUGUGUGAUUGCACGUGCCUGUGGGCCUGGGAUAAUGCCCAUGGUACUCCAUGCAUUCACCUGCCCUGUGCAUGUCUGGACUCACGGAGCUCACCCAUGUGCACAAGUGUGCACAGUAAACGUGUUUGUGGUCAACAGAUGACAACAGCCGUCCUCCCUCCUAGGGUCUUGUGUUGCAAGUUGGUCCACAGCAUCUCCGGGGCUUUGUGGGAUCAGGGCAUUGCCUGUGACUGAGGCGGAGCCCAGCCCUCCAGCGUCUGCCUCCAGGAGCUGCAAGAAGUCCAUAUUGUUCCUUAUCACCUGCCAACAGGAAGCGAAAGGGGAUGGAGUGAGCCCAUGGUGACCUCGGGAAUGGCAAUUUUUUGGGCGGCCCCUGGACGAAGGUCUGAAUCCCGACUCUGAUACCUUCUGGCUGUGCUACCUGAGCCAAGUCGCCUCCCCUCUCUGGGCUAGAGUUUCCUUAUCCAGACAGUGGGGAAGGCAUGACACACCUGGGGGAAAUUGGCGAUGUCACCCGUGUACGGUACGCAGCCCAGAGCAGACCCUCAAUAAACGUCAGCUUCCUUCCUUCUGCGGCCAGAGCCGAGGCGGGCGGGGGUGAGAACAUCAAUCGUCAGCGACAGCCUGGGCACCCGCGGGGCCGUCCCGCCUGCAGAGGGCCACUCGGGGGGGUUUCCAGGCUUAAAAUCAGUCCGUUUCGUCUCUUGGAAACAGCUCCCCACCAACCAAGAUUUCUUUUUCUAACUUCUGCUACUAAGUUUUUAAAAAUUCCCUUUAUGCACCCAAGAGAUAUUUAUUAAACACCAAUUACGUAGCAGGCCAUGGCUCAUGGGACCCACCCCCCGUGGCACUCAUGGAGGGGGCUGCAGGUUGGAACUAUGCAGUGUGCUCCGGCCACACAUCCUGCUGGGCCCCCUACCCUGCCCCAAUUCAAUCCUGCCAAUAAAUCCUGUCUUAUUUGUUCAUCCUGGAGAAUUGAAGGGAGGUCAAGUUGUUUGUCAAUGAUUUGUCAGAGAACCUGUUGAAAUGUGAAUUAAGAAGCUAAGAAAAUAUUUCUUAGCAACAUUUUCUUUUUCUUUUUUUUUUUUUUCUUUUGAGACAGAGUCUCACUCUCGUCGCCCAGGCUGGAAUGCAGUGGUGCGAUCUCGGCUCUCUGCAACCUCUGUCUCCCGGGUUCAAGCGAUUUCCUGCGUCAGCCCCAGAGUAGCUGGAAUUACAGGCACACACCACCACGCCUGGCUAAUUUUUGUAUUUUUAGUAGAGCUGGGGCCACCCUGGCCCGGCCCCGUCUUCCUCCCCAAAGGUCAGACUGCAGGCUGCAGGGCUGUGCUGGAGGAGCCAGCUCUAGCUCACCCAUGCUUUUGCAACAGGGUCGGGUUGGAAGUCAGCACAGGUCAGUCCUGCGGAAGGUUCCUUCGUGACUCAUCUGUGAAGUGGGGUGGUUGGGAGAGGUAGCUGAGAGAAUGCAUGAGAGUCCUCGGUGCCUGGCAGGAGGCUGGAAGGUUCUAGAACACUGAUGGUUAUAAGAGUGGGACUGUGAGCCUGGGAUCGGGGGGUGUGAGACUUGGAUGGGAGCACAAGAGUGGAAACACAGCUUCUGCACGGAGCAGGCGCAGCCCUCAACACCCCGUGCACCUGCACCCUAGGGACUCUUGGGUCCAGAUGUGCUGUGGUUUUCACACCUUCUUGGGGGCAACAGGUUCCAGGAGCCACCUGUGGGUGCCACCUGAGCCACAGGCUCCCAGGAAAGCAGCACAGCUCUCCUGCACCCAGAGCUUGCUGGGUGGCGGAGGGGAACACAGAUGGUUGGGGAAGGCCUGAGGCCAGAUUGGGGGACUCUGGACUGGGGCAGAUGAGGCUCCUCAGAAUCCCACCUUUGAAGGGAACUCAGCUUAUAAACACAGAGGAGCAAAGUUGGAGGGCCGGGCGUAGUGGCUCACACCUGUGAUCUCAGCACUUUGGGAGGCCAAGGAAGGUGGAUCACUUGAGGCCAGGAGUUCGAGACCAGCCUGGGCAACAUAGCAAGGCCCCAUCUCUACAAAAAUUAUUAUUUUUUAAAAAAAUUAGCCAGGUGUGGUGGUGCUUGCCUAUAGUCCCAGCUACUCGGGAGGCUAAGGUGGGAGGAUCGCUGGAGCCCAGGAAUUUGAGGCUGCAGUGAGCUGUGAUUACACCGUUGCACUCCAGCCUGGGUCACAGAUCAAGACCCUGUCUCUUAAAAAUAAAAGUUGGAGACAAGAGCUGGCUCACCUGAAAGGAGGGAUUAGUAGGUAGGAGGGUGGAUGGAGGAUGGAUGGAUGUGUGGGUGGAUAGGAAGAUGGUAUUAAGUUGGUGCAAAAGUCUUUGAUAUUACUCUUAAUGGCUUUAAUAAAAAGCUUGAAGGAAGAAUGAUUGGUUGGAUAGACAGAGAUAAAUGCAUACUGGAAACAAAGAUAAAGAUAAAACACAAGUUAUACCAGGCCAGCAACUCUAUUUUGUUCACUGCCUUUAGUCCCAGCCUGGCACAUAGUAGGCACUCAAUAAAGCCUGAUUUGUAGCA